ACAGAGUUCUCUGCCAUGGCUGGGGACUAGGAAGUGGGAAAGAGCUCUAGGGGAACCUGAGGGCUUGGGUGGAAGACUGGAGAGCCAGGAGGAGCAAGGAGCAGGAAGCAAGUAAAGAAGCCGGCCCAAACCCAUCAAGACCAAGAUGAUGACAUGAGUGACCUCUGAUUGUCCUCACUGCUACACUCCCACCAGCCCCCUGACGGUUUACAGAUGCCAUGGCAACAUCAGGAAGUUACCCUCUAUGCUCUAAAAACGGGAGACACGUGAGUUGUUUCCAGUUUUGGUGACGAAUGCCCAAAUUCAUAGGCGAUGAUAAAUAAUGUGCCAGACGUUGAUGUGCAAGUUUUGGUGUGAGGUGUGGAUUCAUUCAUUCAACAAAUAUUUACGGAACGAACACCUCCUGCGUGCCAGGCUCCAUUCCAAGCACUGGGGGUUGCAGCGGCGAACAAAACAGACCCAAAUGCCUGCCCUGGUGGGCCAGGAAGGCAGAAAUAAAGAUGAAGAGUUGGUCAAGUCUGCAGAUUUCUCAGAGCCUUCAAUGUACUUUGUGAUUCUCCUAUAAGGAAUAAGGUUCAGUCAUCCUUCUGUCUCCCUCUGGGUUUCCAAGAAUCUUACCUUGGAACUCCAAUUGAACUGAGCCCUGGGCUUGUCUGCUGACCUUCUCAACAGUUCUCCAAGCAGCUAUGGAUGUGGGUUUCUCGGGCCUGCCAGAUGUGUCUCAGAGUCAUAGCAAGACCUUGUGGGGGGCUCGGGGCAGGGGCCCCUCCAUACGUCGCCAGCGGGAGUUCAUGCCAGAAGAAAAGAAGGACACAGUUUACUGGGAGAAGCGGAGGAAGAACAAUGAAGCAGCCAAGAGAUCCAGGGAAAAGCGACGUCUCAAUGAUGCAGCCAUUGAGGGCAGGCUGGCUGCACUGAUGGAGGAGAAUGCCCUGCUCAAGGGUGAGCUGAAGGCGCUCAAGCUUCGCUUUGGCCUCCUGCCCCUGACUGGUGGGCCCCGGGCCUUGCCCCUGCAGGCUCUGCUAUUGGAAGCCCCCUGGACUGGGGACCCCCGGCCUGGGGCUGAAGCACUCUCAUCCUUGUCUGGCUCUCACAGCUGCCUCUUAAGGCCACGUUCCCUGGAUGCUGGGAUUCCAGGAUGUCGGGGCUGCCUGCUGGCUCCCAGAUGGACUGGCUUGGCCACUUCUCCUAGGUCCCCCCAAGAGUCUGCAUCUCCUACCCUCAACAGAAUUGACAUGGCCUUGCAGACUGCCCUCCCACCUGCCCUCUUCAGCUGUCACCUCUUGGAGGGGCAUGUAGGGUCCAGACCAGAGCUCAGACCCUGCUGGGGGCUGUGGUCACCAGUGCCCUCUGGAUGCCGGGCUUCAGGGCCAUCAGAUGUGUUGCUGACACCCACUGCUGAUCCCAUGGGUCUGUCUCCUGGGGUGACCUGCCCUGCCCCAGGGAACAGUCCUGAGGGUCUGGGUCAGCCCUCUCUGCCCCACAAACUGCGCAUCAAGUCCCGAGCCUCAGGCAGGGUACCUCGUGGCUGGGAGGGUGGUCAGGCGCCCCUCUGAGGGCUUCCUCUGGGAAGGGCUAGGCUUGCAAGGGGGUGUUUGGGGGCGGAAUAUAGGUUUGUCUGAGGGAUGAGUAGCUUGGUCUUGAUCAGCAAUCUGGGAAGGCCUGUAGGAAGUAGGGGUGCCCUGGCUUGGAAGGUCCACUUCACAGCUUCCAUACCAGACCUCCUAGGGGUGGAGUGGAUGGGAGCCCAUCUUGGAUUCUACCAUGGCUCUUGCCUUGCCUUAAAAUCUAUGCUUUGGGUUGUCACUUUUCCCUCUUCCUUCCUCCUUUCCAUUUAUCUAUUCUUCCCUAUAGCCAUCCAUUCAUCCAUUCAUCCUCAUUUAUUCAUCCAUUCAUUCAUUCAUCAAUCCUUAUCCAUCCAUCCAUUAGUCCCUCCAUCCUUAUCCAUCUAUCCAUCCAUCCAUCCAUCCAUCCACCCAUCUAUUCAUCCAUCCAUCAAUCCAUCCAUCCAUUCCAUCCAUCCAUCCAUCCAUCCAUCCAUCCAUCCCUCCAUCCAUUCAUCCACUUGUCCGUCCAUCCAUCCAUCCAUCCAUCCAUCCAUCCAUCCAUCCGUCCAUCUAUCCAUCCAUCCAUUCAUCCAUCCGUCCAUCCAUUCAGCCAUCCAUCUGUCCAUUUAUCCAUCCUCCAUUUAUCCAUGCAUCUAUUCUCAUUCAUCCAUGCAUUUGUUCUUCCUUCUUUCUAUCUAGCCAUCCAUUCUCAUUCAUCCAUGCAUUUGUUUUUCCUUCUAUCUAUCCAUCCAUCCAUUCAUUCAUCCACCCAUCCACCUAUCUAUGCAUGCAUCCAUCCAUCCUCAUCCACUCAUCCACCCAUCCUCACCUAUCCAUCCAUCCACCCAUUCUUUCUUGCUUCUAUCCAUUUUCCCAUCCACACACCUAUCCAUUCAUCCAUUCAUACAUCAAUUUAUUCUCCAUCCAUCCAUCCAUCCUCAUCCAUUCCCAUUCAUCCAUCCAUCCUGUCUUCCUUCCUUGCAUCCACUCAUCCUCAUCCAUUUACCCAUCCAUCCAUCCAUCCUCACCCAUCCAUCUACACAUCCUUCCUUUCAUCCACCCAUUCAUCUACUCAUCCACCCAUCCAUCCUUUCAUUCAUUUAUUCAUUUAGCCACUCAUUUAUGUGCUAACUUGUUUAUUCAUUCAUUCUCUUACUCAUUAAUUUACUUAUAAUUCACUUGUCCCCUCACCCACCCACUCACGAUCUUUAGACCUUCCUUUUGUGCCCAGUUAGUGACAAGUGAGAAGACACUUUUCUGGUCUUGGGUUUCCUGUCCUGGGGUAGGAAUGGGUGUUUGGGAAGAAACAUACUGAAGACCAGACUGAAGGAGGAGGUAACGUCUAGGGUGUCUGAAUCCCCCUUCUUGGUGUCCCCUGGGGGGCUUGCUUACCACCCAGUUUGAGGGGCAGACAUAUUGGCUUCUUCUGUGUCUUGGAUCAGGCCUUGAGCUGCUGGAACAGGAGCAGCUGUGUGAGGGCAUCAGUGUCCUCUCUCUCCCUGGCUGCCCCCUGCCCCUGAGAACCAGGUAUACACCCACCCAGGUGGAAGGGUCCAUUCUGCAGGGAAGGUCUUCCAGGGGCCUGGAGCCCAAGGACUUAUCAAGGCUCCCUCCUCCUCAGUUUCUCACUCAGCCCCUCUCCCAUUAUUAUUAUUAUUAUUAUUAUUAUUAUUAUUAUUACAUCAGGGAUCUUGUUAGAUUCUAGAUAAAAAUACUCAAACUCCAAUCAUGGGGAGAGCUCAUGGGAUGGGGGGCUCAUCUGGACUGGUACUGACACUGAGAACCAGAUGCCCCUGGCCAACUGGAUCACUUGGACUCAGGAGCAUCGCCCACCCCCACCAGAUCUGGGGGCUGGGCUAGUUCUUGGCUACUCCAAGUUUAUCAGAGCCACAAAUGUGUGCAGGGUGAGGACGUACAAAGUGCCUCUCUCUCACUAGUACAACAGGUGGGCAGUAUCACCAAACAGGCCAAGAGCUCCCCUGUGACUGGGCAUCCCUAGAAUCCUGCACAUCACAGGUAGGACCUCCUCUACUUGCUCAGCCUUUGGUUCUGGUCCAGGGCAGGGAUUGGGCAAGAUCAGCCCUUCUCCUUCCCUCCAUGCCUGACCUUCCAGCAGGUGGCUUUUCUCAUGUCACUGAGCCUCCCUUAUACAUCUAUAAAUGUUUACCUAUAAAUGAGCCCAUUCCCUAGAAAUAUAUUGUGAAUAUUAAAUAAGAGGCAGUAAAUAAAUUGCCCGGUAUAGGGGCUUCUCUGGACUGUUUUAUCUUCAUAAAUAAUGUGAAUCCUGGAGGGCAAGGUGGCUCAUGCCUGUAAUCCUAGCACUUUGGGAGGCCAAGGCAGAUGGAUCUCACUUGAGGUCAGGAGUUCGAGACCAGCCUGGCCAACAUGAUGAAGCCCCGUCUCUAGUAAAAAUACAAAAAUUAGCCGGGCAUGGUAGCGAGCGCCUGUAAUCUCAGCUACUUGGGAGGCUGAGGCAUGAAAAUCACUUGAACCCAGGAGGUGGAGGCUGCAGCGAGCUGAGAUUGCACCACUGCAGUCCAGCCUGGGCGACAGAGCGAGACUCCAUCUGAAAAAAAAAAAAAAAAAAAGGAAAAAGAAAAAAUCCUGUUUCCCUUUUUGCUUUGCCCACCAAGGAGCUCAGGGCCGAGCUUGUGGCUCAGCUAUAACAGCAUUUUCAUUCAUUCAUUCAUUCAUUCAUUCAUUUUUUAAUUCAUUUGCUUAUUUAGCAAAUUUUCUUGAUCAUAAGUUUCUCAUUGUUUCAUUUUAUUCAAGGCAUGUUUUGUUGUAAAAAGUCUGAAAAUCAUAUGCAGCCGAGUUGGCAGUCUUUUCUUUUGUGGUUUGUACAUUUUUGUCAUGUUUAAGACAACUUCCAUGUCUCAAGAUCAUAAAGAUAGUCUCCUAUCUUUAUGUUCCAGGUACUGGGGAAAGAGAAGUGAACACAAUAGAUGUGAUUCCUGCCUCUAUGGUACUGAUAACCCAGGGAAGGAGAUAGAUUAAAAAAUAAGAAAAACAUAUAGUAGGAUCAAUGAUGAUACGUGUCAUGGAGAAAAAAGGGAGGCUUGGGAAAGGUAGGUGUGGGUGCGUUGUAAUAAUUGAAAUAGGGAGAUCAGGAUUGAAAUAGGGGGAUCUCAGCCUUGCUGAGAAAGUGACAUUUGAACAGAGACUUGAGAGAGAUGAAGGGGGGAGUCAUGCAUGUAUCAGAGGAAGAACAUUUCCUAGUCAGAAAGAACAGCCUGUGCAAAGGCCCUGAGGUGGGAUAGUGCCUAGUGUUUUGAGGAAGAUUGAGGAGGCCCAUGUGGCUGGAGUGGAGUGAGUAAGGGGGAGAGAGGGAGGAGGCGAGGGCAGGGAGGUGAUGGAAGCAGGUUGUGGAGGACUUUGUGGGCCAAGGUGAGGACUUUGGCUUCCUUUCUGAGUGAUAUGGGCAUGAGGGGGACGUUUCCAAGUAUAUUUCUGUUGUAGUUCUCCCCUUACCUCCAUCCUGUGAUGUGUGAGGCUGAGUGAAAAUAAACCCACCACAUAAGUGCA